GACGUCAGGGGGCGGUGUCGGAGUGAAUGGGGGCAGCAUGAGGCCGGGCGGCUUUUUGGGCGCCGGACAGCGGCUGAGUAGAGCCAUGAGCCGAUGUGUUUUGGAGCCUCGCCCCCCGGGGAAGCGGUGGAUGGUGGCUGGCCUGGGGAAUCCCGGACUGCCCGGCACGCGACACAGCGUGGGCAUGGCGGUGCUGGGGCAGCUGGCGCGGCGGCUGGGUGUGGCGGAGAGUUGGACGCGCGACCGGCACUGUGCCGCCGACCUCGCCCUGGCCCCGCUGGGGGAUGCCCAACUGGUCCUGCUCCGGCCACGGCGGCUUAUGAACGCCAACGGGCGCAGCGUGGCCCGGGCUGCGGAGCUGUUUGGGCUGACUGCCGAGGAAGUCUACCUGGUGCAUGAUGAGCUGGACAAGCCCCUGGGGAGACUGGCUCUGAAGCUGGGGGGCAGUGCCAGGGGCCACAAUGGAGUCCGUUCCUGCAUUAGCUGCCUCAACUCCAAUGCUUGGCUUGGACUCAUCGUCAACAGCAGCAGCAUCAUCAUCAUCACCAUCAUCAUCAUCAUCAUCAUCAUCAUCAUCAUCAUCAUCAAUGGCUGAGCCCUCACUGUGCUUCCUGGGAGCCGGGCUCAGCUUCCCGCCUCCACGGGCACUACAGGAGGGAACAAAGUCACCUGUCAGGAUCAUGUGGAAAGAGGCCAAGGGUGGAUUUAACCCAGGUAUGCUGAUGCUGAAGUCUGUGCUCCUAACCACUCUGGCCUUCUGCUUCCUGUACCCAGAAGAGAUGGAACCCACAGGCCACUGCUAAAAGUCUCCAACGGUGUUAAAUAUCCUUGGAGGAGCAGGGAAUUCCAAACAACCCAAAGCAUGCAACACCAACUGAGCCAUUCUAAAGCCAGGUCUGUGAGCUGCAGCCAGGCACUGUGCCUUUCCAGAGGCCCUGGUCCAGGCUGCGGGACUCAGCAGAGACUGCUGGGGGCCUGUGCACCCACCUCGGAAUGACACCAAGCAUUUGUUCCUGGAAUUCCCUGCUCCUCCAAGGAUAUUUAACACCGUUGGAGACUUUUUAGCAGUGGCCUGUGGGUUCCAUCUCUUCUGGGUAACACAGGAGGACCAGGGCUUUGGCCAAGAACCUAAAGAGCCACACUCAUUUGCUCUUGGGUGGUAGUGAAGGGGUAGAAUGGAGAGAGGUGACAGGAAGCUGGGACAGAAGACUUCAGAAACAACCAGGGAGAUACUAGAAAGCCACUCCCAGGAGAUUGGAGGGACAGAUGAUCCCGGGAAGCAGCAAACAGUGCUGCUUUUGCUUUAAUGUAAAUUUGGCUUAGAACAAUUUAGAAUUUUAAAAAUUCCAGUCUUGGAUCUCGUUCCAAAGCCUUCUGUUUGCUGGUGAACUAAUGAUAAAGAUAAUGGGGGCCAGACACAGUAGCUCACGCCUGUAAUCCCAGCAGUUUGGGAGGCUGAGGCAGGCCAAUCGCUUGAGCCUAGGAGUUCAA